GUCCUUGUCCCAAGGGACAUACAGCACACAGCCUGUGGAGGGUGGAGGAACCAACUGCAAGUUUCCCAGCUGAAUUCAAACUCAUUCCCAGAUCACUUGUCCUCCUCAAUUGAUGUACACUGAAGAAAGAGCCACCUUCAGGCUGUAAGGUCAUCGUAUAAUCCUGACCACUCAUUUCCCAUCAUGACACUGCUGUUCCUUCUCUUUCUCCUUCUUGGAUGUCUGAUACAAACAGCCUCAGCUUUUCUUAGUGCCUAAAGUGUCUGCAAGUGGAAAUCCAGAGGAAGACAGAGAGAAACUGAGUUCCUGACAAUGCAUUCACUAAAGAAAGUGACUUUUGAAGAUGUAGCUAUUGACUUCACCCAGGAAGAGUGGGCCAUGAUGGACACAUCCAAGAGAAAGCUGUACAGAGAUGUGAUGCUGGAAAAUAUCAGUCACCUGGUGUCCCUCAGGUACCAGAUAAGCAAAGCCUAUAUAAUUUUGCAGCUGGAGCAAGGAAAAGAGCUGUGGCGGGAAGGAAGAGUAUUUCUUCAAGACCAGAAUCCAAACAGGGAAAGUGCCCUUAAGAAAACACACAUGAUAUCCAUGCAUCCUAUCAUCAGAAAAGACGCAUCCACCAGUAUGACAAUGGAAAUCCCACUUCCAACUGGAUGUCUGGAUGAACUACUGAAAGCUGCUGAGUGUCCUGCAGCAGGCCAUUUCCAAUCCAGCGGAAGACCUUCUAGAAGAGAUGAUGGUGGGAGAGUGCUGACAUACUAUGUGAAGCUACUAUUUGGAGUUGGACACGAGUGCAUGUGUCCUUGUGCCACAACGGGAAUCUUGACUACAACACAAAUGAAUCCACUCAAAUGUUGGCAAGUGGAGCAGAGUCCCAGAACAGUCUGCAAUCUCUACAGGUACAGAAACACCCCCAGUUCAAGGAUCUUCACACCUGGAUUUAGGCCUACUCCUGCAACUACCCCAGGGGGUAAUAUUGAGUUCCAGAAGGCAAGGAUUAACAUUCAGAAAAUAGGAAAAACAACCUGCAGCUACUUACACCAAGAUGAAGAUAAUUUAUUAGUUCAGGAAGAAUCUGCAUUCUGAAGACAAAUAGAAGUUCCAGCUACAGAUGGGCAGACACAUGCCCUCUCAAUUCCUGAUGGACCUCCUAGUGCCUUCUGGACCUAAGGGGCCUCCCUCAAUGUUCCAAGAUGCCACCAAGGCAGGGAUCAGCUCGUGCAUUCCUGAGAACAUCCCGGAUGAAGUGAGGCUCUGGAAAAAUGCAAGAGUUUCCACAUAAUCCCAAAAAACACUACAGGUGAACUGGAUGCCACAGAAAGAGGAGUGGUCUUUGUCACAACGAAAUCAACAAAAUUAUUUCGAAGUCAAUUAGGAAACUCAGAAAUCACUCUUGCUACCAUUAAGAGGAAGAACAGGAGCCUGUGAAUGGCAUCCCUGGCCUACCUGAGACUCCAAAGAUAUUUCUCUGUGGCUUCUGACAGCAGAAAUCUCUGUGAUUUUCAGAAAGGUAGGGACAGCUCCUGCCAGCCCAUCCUUCUGCAGAAUGUGUCCCAGCAGAUCAGUGGCAUGGAACCAUCAUGGACAGCACAAAGGCUCAAGGGCAGCAUCCCAGGCCGGCCUGUGACUCUAGAUAAGUUCUGAGUCCCCAUGGGGGCUCAGGAAAGGUUAGUGAUGACCUGGAAAGAAGGGACAGGCUGAAACCGCCCCUAAGCAAUCUGCAGGAUUCCAACUUCAGCAGGAAGCCAAGGACCAGCUAUUACCACACCUGCGCCCCCUGAAAACGCUGGAUACAAUCCCACUCUGCAGAAAGUUCCACAUAGAAGUGGCUGGGAAUUUUGCCUUCUAGACUGCAUUUUACACUGCCUCUGGACAUGUGAUGAGAAAUUUAACAUUGGUGUAUCUAACUCUGACAUUUUUCACGAAGUGAUUUUUUAAAAUAUGGUAAAAAAGACAAAAUAUAAUUCAAACAUAUGCAUUAUAUGUCAAAGUAUGCUUCGCUGGCAUCAAGUAGACUCACCUUGAGAUACAAUCUUGGACAACCUCCAUCUUCAGAAUAUCUAGUUUUUCAAACCAAAACUCUCCAACCAAAAAUCAAUAACAUCAAAAGUUUGCAACUACAAGCCGACGGAAAAUAAAUACAUGAAUUCUACCACAGUGAAUUGGACUGCACUGGGAAACACAGAUGAAGAAAGCCAACACCGCUUUGUCCUUCAGUACCUGGCUCCCUUUUCAGCUCGUCUUGCGACUCCAGGCAUUAUGCCUGAAAAGUCUCCUGGACGCCUGUGAGGCUCUAAUUCCCUGGGACCCAUUGUCAUGUCUCUGGAUUUGCGAAGAUUAACCGGACCUUCUGUGGAACUCCCGUGUCCCUCAACUUUUGUGACAUGUCCCCUAAUUCUGCCCAUGGUCAUCUGCACCUGCACGACUUAGGGUCCAUGUUCCUUGGACGGGAAGAGACAGGCAGGAGUCGGAAUGAUGAACCAGCACACUGGGGCAUUUUCUCAUGUAGCCCAAGUGACCCCAUGGUCUUCUUGAGCUUUGGAACCAGUCGCGUCCCCCUUGACACUGCACCCGACUCCCAGUUUCUCAAUCUUGUUGGCCCUCCGGCGAUCUCCCGUUGGAUGAAUUGCAUCUGCUGAAACUCGAGUCCCCUUUGAUUUGUGCUUCAUUAAUUAUUCAUGAUUCAGGUUGGAAGGCCUGCUGACGACCCCCUGUGGCCGUUUUCCGAGCUUUCCGGUCACAUCGUUUCCUUCCACCCUCUUUGGUUCCUUGUGGUCCUGCUCCUUCUGCUGUCAGAGGAGCAGAGAGUUGAUCUUAUUGAUUCUGGAUACGGAUACUUUGUAGGUGAUCUGGAUAAUCAAGAUAACGACCCUCAAAAGCGGCGGAAAGGGAGCAGCCAUUUGGUGUGUCUCAGCAAAUCCCGCUGAGUUCCGAGGCCGCCUAGGUAUGCAAUCCUGCUGAGAGUUGUUCCCAGGUCAGAGAAUGGAGAGAGCCUGUGCAUGAUGGGAUAUCCCUGCCUAGAUCUUUCAGUGAGUCUCUACCUCAGCUACUCUUAGGAUCAGGGGGAGAACCAUGGAAAGGCCCGGUGUCAGACAUCCGGAAAGAAGAGGGAUGAAUGUUUCACCUCUGAAGUACAUCCCAAAUGUGGGAGUUAACUUCAGCUUUGCUGGGGUCUACUUGGCCAGCGAAACUCUGCCUGGUUCAUUCGCACAUCCGGAAGCCACUUCACGGGGAGCCGUCGCAACCGGAACCACACACUUGGCAUCGGCGGUUGAGCCAAAUGGGGACUCGUGGUGCAAGCAACGCUCCCCACGUGUUAGCGUGCGUGAGAUUCAAUUGGCGGAAUUUUACUAGGUGCGUGUUGGUAGAGCGGGGCUGAGGUUUUCUUGCUCCUGUGGAUGUAUAGGAAGUCAAAGGUCCUGCCCAGCCCUGCGGUCCCCUCAGUCAACUCUGUUUCGGAGACAUAACGAUUUGGAUUGCUAACAAGUCAAGAAAUGUUCAAGUCCUUGGAUGUAGGGAAAAGAAAGAGAGAUCAGACUGUCACUGUGUCUAUGUCGAAAGGGAAGACAUAAGAGACUCUAUUUUGAAAAGGACCUGUACUUUAAACAAUUGCUUUGCUGAGAUGUUGUUCAUUUGUAGCUUUGCCCCAGCCACUUUGCCCCAGCCGCUUUGACCCAACUUGGAGCACACAAAAACCUAUGUUGUAUAAAAUCAAGGUUUAAGGGAUCUAGGGCUGUGCAGGACGUGCCUUGUUAACCAAAUGUUUACAAGCAGUAUACUUUGUAAAAGUCAUUGCCAUUCUCUAGUCUCAAUAAACCAGGGACACAAUGCACCGUGGAAAGCCGCAGGGACCUCUGCCCUUGAAAGCAGGGUAUUGUCCAAAGUUUCUCCCCAUGCGACAGUCUGAAAUAUGGCCUCGUGGGAUGAGAAAGACCUGACUGUCCCCCAGCCUGACACCCGUAAAGCGUCUGUGCUGAGGUGUAUUAGUCAAAGAGGAAAGCCUCUUGCAGUUGACAUGGAGGAAGGCCACUGUCUCCUGCUUGCCCCUGGGAACUGAAUGUCUCGGUGUAAAACCCGAUCGUACAUUUGUUCAACUCUGAGCUAGGAGAAAAGCUGCCCUGUGGCGGGAGGCGAGACAUGUUGGCAGUAAUGCUGCCUUCUUAUUCUUUACUCCGCUGAGAUGUUUGGGUGGAGAGAGACAUAAAUCUGGCCUACGUGCACGUCCAGGCAUAGUACCUUCCCUUGAACUUAAUUAUGAUAUAGAUUCUUUUGCUCACAUGUUUUUUGUUGACCUCCUUAUUAUCACCCUGCUCUCCUAGUAUAUUCCUUUUUGCUGAAAUAAUGAAAAUCAUAAUCAAUAAAAACUGAGGGAACUCAGAGGUCGGUGCAGGUCCUUGGUGUGCUGAGUGCCGGUCCCCUGGACCCACUGUUGUUUCCCUAUA